AACAAUGGGACUUCCACAGCAAUGGGAUCGGCUUCCUCUUUCAGUGUGUGCCUUUUCUAUGAGCGAGAGACUCCUAGGAAAGCAGCAGCCCAUUAGGAAAACGUGUGGGAACUCACUCGCAGCCUGGACUCUGAAAUGGGCAUGUACAGAGACGAAGAGACCCCAACAUGCUUCAGGCUUUGAGUGGAGAGGACACAGCCUCUGCUGGGACAGGGAACAGAGGGAUGUGGAGUCCCUGAAGAUGCUUUUGGACAAUGGUCUGAGGUUGGGACAGUGGCAGGAGAUACCAUUCACCCAGGAUCUCCAGGACAAGAGAUCAGCCUGGCAGUUACAUGUGUUUUUUUUUCAAACUGGUUGCCAGGUUGGCAUGAACGAUGACAUCAGAGAUUCCGACCUUCCUGAUUGGAGGGACCGGACUCCGUGGUGCCUGGAGAUCAGUUGGACAACAGUAUCUUCUCAGAGCUGUUCUCCACUCCUGACUUCUCCUAGGCUUGAGAAUUGAUAACAUACUCUUCUGGAUCCUAGCAGUGUCCAGAAGAAGGCCAUGGACAGAACGGAGACUAGGUUCCGUAAGAGGGGACAGAUUACGGGAAAGAUCACGACCAGCCGUCAACUGCACCCCCAGAAUGAGCAGAGUCCCCAGCGGAGCACCUCGGGGUACCCCCUCCAGGAGGUGGUGGAUGAUGAAGUGUUGGGACCAUCAGCCCCUGGGGUAGAUCCCAGCCCCCCAUGUAGGUCCCUUGGCUGGAAAAGGAAGAAGGAGUGGUCAGAUGAAUCUGAGGAGGAGCCGGAGAAGGAGCUCGCCCCUGAGCCUGAGGAGACCUGGGUAGUGGAGACGCUGUGUGGGCUUAAGAUGAAGCUGAAGCAACAGCGAGUGUCACCCAUCCUCCCUGAGCACCACAAGGACUUCAACAGUCAGCUUGCCCCUGGGGUAGAUCCCAGCCCCCCGCAUAGGUCCUUUUGCUGGAAAAGGAAGAGGGAGUGGUGGGACGAAUCUGAGGAGUCGUUGGAGGAGGAGCCACGGAAGGUGCUCGCCCCUGAGCCUGAGGAGAUCUGGGUGGCGGAGAUGCUGUGUGGCCUCAAGAUGAAGCUGAAGCGACGGCGAGUGUUGCUCGUGCUCCCUGAGCACCACGAGGCCUUCAACAGGCUGCUUGAGGAUCCUGUCAUUAAAAGAUUCCUGGCCUGGGACAAAGAUCUGAGGGUGUCGGACAAGUAUCUCCUGGCUAUGGUCAUAGUGUAUUUCAGCCGGGCCGGCCUCCCCUCCUGGCAAUACCAACGCAUUCAUUUCUUCCUGGCUCUCUACCUGGCCAAUGACAUGGAGGAGGACGACGAGGACUCCAAACAAAACAUCUUCCACUUCCUGUAUGGGAAGACCCGCUCUCGCAUACCCUUGCUCCGUAAGCGUUGGUUCCAGUUAGGCCGUUCCAUGAACCCGAGGGCCAGGAAGAACCGCUCUCGCAUACCCUUGCUCCGUAAGCGUCGGUUCCAGUUAGGCCGUUCCAUGAACCCGAGGGCCAGGAAGUACCGCUCUCGCAUACCCUUGGUCCGUAAGCGUCGGUUCCAGUUACGCCGUUGCAUGAACCCGAGGGCCAGGAAGAACCGCUCUCAGAUAGUCCUGUUCCAGAAACUUCGGUUCCAGUUCUUCUGUUCCAUGAGCGGCAGGGCUUGGGUUUCCCCGGAGGAGUUGGAGGAGAUCCAGGCUUAUGACCCAGAGCACUGGGUGUGGGCACGAGAUCGCGCUCACCUUUCCUAGAGCUCCAGGGACCGUGGAGGCCUGAGGUCAUCGGCCUGAGAGAAGAACACCGGACCCAGGGGAGAUGUGGAUUUUCAGCAGGAACUUUAUUCCAAUGCUAAUGGCAGACACCAGGAAGGAGAAGAGGAACCAUUUGUGCAGAUCAUCUAGAAGAACCUGGACCAUUCUUGAUGGAGCUGAAUACAGUGAUCACGUGUCCUCCUGGGAGCAGGGGUUGGGGGAGGGGGGUGGGGUCCUUCUAGGAGUCCUUGGAGAAAAGUAAGAAACCAGGAGUGUUUCCAGUUCCACCCUUUCCUGCGGCACCACCACCCUUUUUAUAUUGCUGAAUUCCAACCUCCCUGGGGCGGAACCUGGAGGUGCUGUUUCUUACGGACUUGGUUGCCACAGUCCAGGAGCAUUUGAAGGCACAAUGCAGGGGCUCAGAUUGGCACAGAAUUCUUUUGUGAAAUAUCAGUGCCACAGAUUGUAACAGAUAGCUUCAUGCACACUCUGCAUUUUAUUGGUUUGUUUGGAAAAUGUUGGCCAUUGAAUUAUUCAUAGAUUUAUUUCAAAUAGUUUGGAAAUUGUUGUACUUUUGAAAACAUGCUGUUCCUGUAGUUUUUUGAUGAGAGUUAUAGUUGUUAUAUAUACAUAAAGAUAAUUUUCUUUUCAUUUUUAAGAGACAAUUCUUUUUAUCCUAAAUAUUUUAUUAUCUUUAAAUUUUUUUCUGUAUUAUUAUAUGUGCUCCUGAAGCGAGCACUCUUUUUAUCUAUGAUACUUCCAUAAUAAUCUCUUCUAUUUAUAGCUAUUGGUAGUUCCCCACCAGAAAAAAACAUAAUUCUGGUGAUAGAAAUUUUUAUUUGCUGUUUAGGUUUGUGACUGAAUUGUGAGAAUUCAGUUGUGAUUUUUAACAUGUCUCAGAUAUAUAUACUAACACGUCUAAUAUAUACUAUCUAUUUUAUUGGUUUAUUUUGAAAAACAUGGGUAUAGAAUUAUUUAAAUAUUAUUUUAUUUAUUUAAAUAUUUAUUAAAUAUAUUUAUUUAUUUAAAUAUUAUUAUUACUUUAAAUAUUAUUUUAAAUAUUUUGGAAAUACUGGUAUUUUUGAAUAGAUGCUGUUUCUAUAAAGCUGUGUGAUGGGUAUUAUAACUGUUAUAUACACAUACAUAUAAUUUUGUUUUCCUUUUUAAGAGAGGAUUCUUUUCAUCCUAAAUCUUUUACCUUUCAAUCUUUGUAUCUAUUAUUACACGUGCUGCUGAAGGGAGCAUGUUUUUAUCUAUGAUACUUAGUUAACAUAUAUAUUACAUUUAUAGCUAUGUAGUAGUUCCCCUAAAUUCUUGUAAAAAUAAAUUUUUAUUUGAUAUUUCAUAUAUAUUUGAAAUGUGAGAAUUCAGAUGUAAUUUUUUACCUUGUUUUGGCAUGUUUGUAUAUUACUUUAAAGAGGAUGUGUGUUCUAAAGGAGGACAUGAGCUGUGUGUUUUCAAGAGAACAAUAGAGUGCGUCUCUUGGGGAAACAUAAUAAAAAUGAACUUUUCUCACCUUCACAGCAAUUGUGA